GCUUGCUGCCACCCAUCACCACCCCCCUCUGCAUCGGUCGGCUCAGGACUUACGGAAACAGGUAAAGUCCAGCAGGGGUGCCUACAUGUGUGCCAGACCCCAGUUUCCCACUUCACUUCACCAAGCUAAAAAUUCAUCUUCAGAGGGCUCAAGAAGCAGGAGGUGAUGCCCAGAAGCAAGACAGGGACAGACAGAGCGCACCUUUGCAUGAGCUGCAGGCGCCUGCACCUUUUGUCCUGCGAAGAUCCAUCAGUUGGAUUUGCAUUCAUCCCUGGGUGCCACUGCAUUCACCAAGAAAGUGAACUCACUUUUUUACUUAAGCCUUCUCCCACCCACCCACCCUGGGCUCCAGAUGAGCGGUAGAGUGGCAGGGAACAUGUUUUUCUCAGGGUAGGUUUUGAAACACACCUGCAAAUGGGAUAGUUCUGUUAAUGGAUGAUCCUGGUCUACUUUUCUGUUCUUUUUGAUGUGACAAGUUAACAUUUCACCACCUGGCCUUUGAAGCAGAAUAUGUGCAUGCUGUGUGCACUGCCGAGCAGUCUGUGGAACUGGGUGUGGCUGGGUGGCACCUCUUCCACUGAAGGCAUUUGAGUCCCAGGCUGUAGCAUCCACAGAGUGUAGGUGGCUGCCACCCUGACCACCUCCUGCCCCUGCCUGUCCUGCGCUGUCCCCCCACCCGCUAUCCCCCAACAGGGCCACAGAUAAUGCCGGUUCUGGUGAGGCAGUUUUGAAGAAUCCCUCAGGGCUUGGCCAUUAUUGCUGUCCAGAUGUUCCCAUUCCUGGACAUUGAUUUCUCACAACCCUAGGGAUGAGUAGUGGGGAUAAGGGCAGGUUCCUGCAGGCACACAGCUGAGGGCUUGUCCCCGGACAGGUGGCAUUUCACUGAUGCCUCGUGCUCCUGUUCCCCCCUCCAUUUUAACAUCCGCUAAGUCAUGGGAUCAUUGAUGAGCUUUCCUCACAGAGUUAAAAAUAGAGGGUUAAAAUCUUCCCUAGAAGAGACUGGAGGCUAUGAUCCUUAAAGGUAGCUUCAGAGGAAGUUGUAGAGGGGACGGAAGAGAUUUCCUGGCUGGCAGUGUUGCAGAGUGACUUACAUGGUUAUUGUGGUGUGAAAAUACUCGAUUUCGUCUUGCGGUAGAGGUGGCCUUUCUCAUUCUUGGUGACGUUGUGGAUAUUUCUCUCUGAACGUGAACAUGUGACUAUAGUCACACAUAGGCAGACAGGUAUGUAUGCAUGCACAUGUGAACCUUUACCUAGCAAAUAGUAUGCAGUUGGGGGGGUGGGCAUGGCAAGAAUCACCACAUUUACAUUUCCACAGUCCACACACACCUAGCACAUAUUAAACACUGGCCACUGUUGGCCAAAACAGACCUCAGUUUUCCCAGAGACAACAGCCACGGUGUGGAAUUGGGCCACACCAUGUGCUCACCUGGCGUCUCUUAACCAUUGGGCCCCGGAUUGUCAGCACUGGAGGCACAAAGCCCAGGGAGGCACCGAGCUUUGGUCCUGGGUCUGUGAUUCUUCACUCCCCCGCUGUUCCCAAUGCUGUUGGUCUGAUGGAGAAUUGUACAGAACUCUCCAAUGUGUAAGGUUUUUGCUCAUGAAAGAGAACAGAAUUAGAAGCAACCCAGGGAGAAAGACAGAAAGACAGUGAUUACACCAUGUGACUGCAUCCUGUCUCCUUUCCCAGAAUCCUAGAGUAGGGUUAAGUUGUUUUUGUUUAUCUUCUAUUCAUCCCACUAUGCUUUUUUGAGUUUUUUUAGUUUACUUGUGGUAAAAUUCUCAUGGGCCACAUCAGAACUGGAGGCCAUAUCCAGGUGAGCUUCCAGAUCUUGCCUUUCUGCCCUGAGAACCCAUCCUUGGGAUGGCGAGGCAGGAAUGAAGGGUGGCAGAGGACCUGAGUCAUGUACAUGUGACUGUUCAUGUUCUCAUGCACGGACAGACACGGGUGCGCACAUCCUCUUGCACGGUCACGAAUAGGGAUGCGUGGGAUACGCCUGUCAUCUCAGCUGGUCAGAGCUCACUCUCAGCACUUGGCCUUCAUUCAGUUCAAGGUUUUCAUUUGUAAGGGGAUGAGAGGAAUUAGUACAGUUGGACAGAGGAAAGAGCUGAGGAGGAACAGAAAGUACUGCCUUAGCCUGGGAUGGCCCUGCCUGCCCCCAUGCUCCAUGGCGUGUUCGUGUGACCUGUUCCCUGUGCAGGAUCUUAGGUGCAGGAAAGAGGUCCUGGGGUGCCCCUCACACAGCCGGCCUCUGUCCUCUGAGUUAGUGCAGGAGUUUCAGCUGCUUCCGGGGCUCAGGGUAGAGUCCUUGCAGGGAGCGCCAUGUGCUCAUGCAGGGCAUCCUGCAGGUGUUGACGGGGAUCCUCUCCUGUCACCCUUUCCCCACUUUCUCCCUCUUCCCUCUCCUCCUCCUUCCCUGUUCCAGUCUAACCAGCCCAGAUGGGUUGACCCAUGGCUCCAGAUUCUAAUUUGGCUCUGACUCUGACCUUCAAUGAGACUUGAGAUGUGAUAUUUAACCUUCCUGGGCCCUAUUAUUCCUUUGGAGCCAGUCUGGCCAACUCCUUAUACCAGGGACAUUGUGAGAAAUAAAAGGAAAAUUUUCAAACCCUCAGAUCCUAUUAGUUAAGUACUCUGAAAAUAAGGUCAGUAAAAGCAAAUUGUAGAUUCCCUUGUGACUGCUUGAUACAAGUGAUUAGACUGUGACCUUUCAUCUUUUCAACUGCAUGAAAGAUAUGGGCCCAGAGGAUACUCUGAUCUUUCAUUUCAAAUAUGAUAUGUGGAUUUUUUUUUGUUAUUGUUCAGCUUAAAAGCAUAAAUGUGACUGUAUUGAAAUGUGGAGGAAUGUAAUUUUUAGGGGGUGCUGCCGAGAAGUGCCUUUGCUCUGCUUGCUAUAAUGAACUGUGUGGGUGCAUGCACCUGUCUUCCAAGUCUAAAACCACUUCCCCUCGUGCGAACUGGGCAAUGCCAUUUGAUAGUGUGUGCGAUUUAUGGAGUCCCUAGAACCCGAGAGUUAGAACACACCAGUGCGUACUUCACCUAAGCCUUUUUCUUGGUGAGAGGGCUCUGGCCCCGGCCGUUUACUCUCGAUUAUACCAAAUGAGCUGUCUUUGUCAUGGAAUGCACAUGCCUGUAUAACAUUGCAUUGUCAUGGGGCUGGGAGUGCCCCUGGGUAAUAAUUUGGUUGUAUGGUAAGGGUCUCACCAAGGAGCAAAUGGUGUUUUUCUGUUGCUUUCCUGCAGUAGUACUUCUGCUUACAUGCAGUGACAGAAAGUAACAAGUUUAGGAUAGUCCAACAGACGAGCUUUAUUUCUAGCAAGGGUUUUGAAGUAUUAGUUUUCCAAGAGAGUCAUGAGCAGGUUUUGUACUUGUGUAGAAAUUUGUGUGGUUUGUAAGCCAGGAUAUUGAACCAGAUGUGGCCACAUGUGAUUCUCAUUUCUUACGCUGAGGCUGAGUGUGAGAAGAAAAUGAUCAACUGGCUAAUCCCACUGGUUUUGCAGGACCUUCCAUUGAGCUAUAGGCUACUGUCACUGAAGAGGUUUUCAUAUGAAAAUGUACAAGCCUUGCAGAAAAAUCCUGCCCUAGUAAGAUUCAGAGAGGGCCAAGGAAUUGAGAAUAUUCUUUUAAAGUUCUGGAAAAUACGGCUAUUGAGAAGGAAACAUAGAAAAUCAUAUUAGUUUUUAAAAAAGUUAAAGGUUUUCUUCUCAUGACAUUAUUUUGUCAUUUGAAUUGCACUUGCUGGUGGUGGGGUAUUUGUGACUCAGUUACAUUGCCUUCAGUGGGAGGAGAGGUUAUAGGUACAUCUAGAUUGCCCAGUGGAACCCAGGCAUCUCUUUUAGAGCACAUUUGCCUUGGCCUUGGCCUUGGCUAGGAGGCUCCUGCCCAUCUGCUGCUGCGGUCAGUGUUUGAGCAGGCUGCUCCUCCCCUUCCAUAACUCACUGUCUGUCCAGUGCAUUUCGCUUCUGUUUAGGCUCUUUGUUUUUGAUUCAAGUUUUAAAGUGCAAAUGGACUACCCCCAGCCACCAACUGUUUCUCUCUCUGGGCCUCUGGUUCUGUUUUGAAAGGCUGGCAGAGGCCUCGGCUCAACGGCUCCCUCUCGUGGAGAAGAAGAACUUGCCAGUGAAUCUGAGGUUGAACUGAGGACAGCGUCAUAAUCUUGAACGACUAAAACAUUUUUGCUUAGUUAACCAAAAACAUCAGAGUCAUUUCUCAUCUUCUGCUCUGCCUUGGAAGUGCAUGUUUCUCCUUUUCAUCUGUCAUCAUACUGAGUUGAUUUAAAUAUUGUGUGUGUCGGUGGUGGGGUGGAGAAAAACCCAUAAGGAUGGAGGGGAGAGAUUUUAUAUUCUUAAAGCAAGCACACAGAGUGUGGAUUGGGUACAGUUUUUAAGAUGGAAUUUCUGUUAUUAAGAACAAAGUCAGGUAGGAACGUUUGAUGUCCUGGACUUUCAUAUCUCUCACCUUAUAUCCCUUCUGCAAGAAGAAUGAGGUAUUGUUGCCAGUACUCAUCUGGCCGAACGUAACUUGAAAAUGCUCUCAACCUUGCCUGUUAAAUUGAAACCAUUCUCUUAUGACUAGGAGGGAUUGCUUUAAUAUCUCAUGGCCGUGUGCCUGGGAUCACCUGAGAUACAGGUGACGGAUGGCUGUGGGCCAAGGAGCACACGCUGCAGACACCUCACUUUCUGCAGAGCUGGGUUGGGGGCUGGGGGCAAUGGGCUGAGAAGCCAGAAAUCCACAACAGAGCUGAGAGAAGGAGUAACUUCAAGCACUUAUGUAUAAAGCUGCUCAGCUGAAAUGUAUUGUCAUUCAAUGGAGGGUCCUGCUGUAGCCCACGUCGGCGCUAAUUCUUCAGUGAGUUCAGAUGACUUCCUGUGUGUGCUCUUCUGUGGAAUCCCUCAGGACGUGCAGCGGUGGCCUUCCUUGUAGUGCACUGGCUGCAUAACUGGGGCUGUGUGGUUUUAAUUGAUACAGAGGUGGGUUGAGGGAGACCUUCGGUAACAAGGUAAGACAAUGCCUUCCUCCAUUCUUCUGUUUCCUUUUGUACUGAUUAAGUGUUGGCUCCUUAUAGACAAGUCCAGGCCAGGAAAAGGGGUGUCCUUUUGUUAGAUUGGUGGGUCCCAGGUUUCCCCACAAUGGUGGUGCUGGCUGGGUUGUUGGUUCUGUUUUAUUUCUCCCUUUUAGGACACAUGGAGCAGCUUAAGGGGCUUCCUAUGUUAGCUUUUCAGCUCCCCUGUGGCCUCUCGUGGUGGGCAUAGAACACGGACCCUCUGGGUUUCGAGGAGGAAGAUGGCCAGUGACACUUGCCUUUUUCAGUCUUCGUAAUUGUUUGAACUUCGCUGGUCUGUGUUGUGGGUGAGAUCCAUCUAGUCUUUGAGCUUGUUAUAUGGGCAUGCGUGUGUGAUAUCUGGGUGGAUACUGUUGAAGAUAACUCCUAUAAUAAGAAGGAAAAUAUUGCAACUCAUUUCUCUCAUAAAGCAAGUUAUUUGAAUGUAUACCUUGCCAAUAAUUCAGUAUUUAGGUUUUCAGAAAGAUGUAAACAAGGUGUUCCUUUUGCCAUUGAAGAUAGUGAUAUAUAGAAUUCAGCUGUGUUGAAAAUUUACUUCCCUGUAGCAUUGCUAGCCAUGAACUCAGGUGCCCCCGAGAAGCCAGAAUGGAUGGAACCAAAGGCCUUACACUCUUAUUUGAGAUAGAAUAUGAGAGACAUAGCACUCUGGUAUUUGGACAGCGGUGUUAGGGAAGGGUAGGGUCCACGGAUUUGUGGGAACACUGAGACAUCUGAGGCUUUUAAACACUGAUUCCCUUUCUUGAUCCUCACCAAUUAGCACAGAAUCUAGAGGGAAGGGAUUUACAUUAUUUUGAAGCUCCCCUAAGGGUUUUAGGGGUGCCAGGUUUGGAAAACACUGAACUAAACCUCAGCAAGUAGUGGUGGCUGAUGCCUGAACCUCACAGGAGUUGGGUUAUGUCCGGCACCAUCUGGAGUUUGCCAUUUUGAUUAGCGAUAUACGAAGCCGCACUGUGUCCGUCUCCUUAAGGAGACUCUUGUGCUGGGAGUAGGGCUGAAACAGAUUGCACCCCUACAGGUUAAAAGGAGAUUGAGCCAACUGUAGAGGUGUUGUCUUUUGCUGUCUGAACCUGAGAUAGAGCCCUUCCCCAAGGUCCUGGAUUCCCUGAGGCCCAUUCCCCCACCCCCACCCAGCCCCACCAGCCUUUGUUGCUGGAAAUAAAGAUCAGCCCCAGCUGGAGUUUACUGUUUGCUUUUGUUUUUCUAAAUGUUUUGUCUUGUUUUGGUUUUAGUGGAAGCAUUUGAAAGAACAAUUAAAACUAAGAGAUUUGCAUUCCUCACUAUACCUCCUCUUGCAGAUUAACAGUACUUACCACGGAAUAUUUCUGUUUGUCCUUACCCCUGGUUUUAUAAAUCUGUUUUAAAUUUAUCAUUGCCAGGUGCUUUUUUUCCUCUCCAAAAGGGUUUCGCAUUAUUUAUUCCAGACCGUCUGUCAGUCCCACUUUUUUUAUGGGUGACUCAUGGUUUAAGAGCCAGAGUGUGAUUCCUGGGUCUUCGCUUCUGCCUCUUCAUGGGGCCUGAGAUCUGGCUCUAGGAAUGAGGCCUCCAUGGGCCUGGCUCCUAAGAGAUGAUGUCCUACCAAGAAUUUGUGGCUUUGAUUGGACUGCACUUAAUUGGUGGCAUAUAGAGAAAUACAGGUCUCAGUGGCUUCUUUCCUUUUUGAUUUUUAUAAACUUCACUGAUACUUCAUUCAGUGGUUCCAAGCGCGGUCCCCAGGUCAGCACACAGCAUCACCUGGGACUUGGUUAGAAAUGCACAUUCUCAGUCCCAUCCCAGACCCUCUGACUUGGACACUCUGCCGGUAGGGCCCAGUGAUGUGUUUACAUCAGCCCUCUAGGGGAUGCUGAGAGCCACUGGUUUGGAUGUUUUUGGCAAGUCUUUUUUUUUUUUUUUUUUUUGAGACAAGAGUCUCGCCCAGGCUGGAGUGCAGUGGCAUGAUCUCGGUUCACUGCAAACUCCACCUCCUGGGUUCACGCCGUUCUUCUGCCUCAGCCUCCCAAGUAGCUGGGACUACAGGCGCACACCGCCACACCCAGCUAAUUUUUUGUAUUUUUAGUAGAGACGGGGUUUCACCGUGUUAGCCAGUAUGGUGUCAAUCUCCUGACCUUGUGAUCCACCCGCCUCGGCCUCCCAAAGUGCUGGGAUUACAGGCGCCUUUGGGAAGUUUCAUUCCAUGCCCCACCCCCACUUAAGGGGGGUCCUGGGCCAGGCCUAGGUUUAGUACAAAGGUCACUAAGACUCAUUACCCGCCAUCUGGGGACCUUCGUCCCCAUGUGACAGCAGCCUGCACAGCCUUGUGGUGGCACUGGUGUUUCAGUACCCUCUGGGCCAUCACUGCAUGUGGCCAGCUCUCCUGACCAGGAAGUGCAGGCUCCCCCGACCCUGGCACCUUCCUCUCGGGCUGUUGGGGAGAAGAGGGGGCUAGUAUUCUGUGUUUCUCAGUAAUUUUGUGAUUUUUAGGCUUCUUCCUUUGGAGAUGGUGGUGGUUAUAAAACCCUGAAGUCCCUGACUUUAACCUCAUAUCAUAGACGAAAAGUAAUGCCCAAGGUGUUAAGUGAUGGGGCAGUGGCCACAUUGUGACGCAGAGAAGACAUCUUCUCGAAACCAGCAUGUCUGGCAGCAGCCCAUUGGGGUCCCUUCAUUAUUCUUGUUUGAAGCUUGUGCAUUUCUAGUGUCUGCCAUUGUCGCUCCCCAUUUUCGCUGACGUUUGUGUGUCCCAAGAUUACCACGGCGUCCAAGCUGUAAGACUGUCUCUGUUUGCCCAGGUCCCAUAGAACCUGAUGGGAAAGUUUGUCCAGGGUGGAAGAUACAUGGGACAGUUUGUAAACGGUGGGAAAAUAUAGGAAGCGCGUGUGCAGACGAGGGUUGGCAUGUGUUGCUUCAACAGUGAGGUCGGGGCAUCCCUCUUCCAUCCAGCCUGGCCCUGUCCAGGGCUCGUCUCCACAAGGAAAGCAGACAGCAGCUGCUGACAGUUUGCAGCCACACCUCUGGGCCUGGCCUGCCACCCGGAGCCAAACCACAUGAGCACUGCUGUUCUUUUGCUUCCAUAGUAUUUUUGUUUUCCUUCUUUUUUUAGCCAUAGAUUUCUAAAUCCUGUGGGCAGGUCAUGCUGCUAUGUGGAGCACAGAAAUAGCAGACAUGACUUUUCUUGGAACAGGGAUAUGUGUGUGUGUCUGUCUCCACUUCCCCCAAGGAAGCAGGAUCUUGCUGUCAUCAACUCUGAGAAGCUCAGGACAGGUGAUUGCAUGGCACGUGGGGAGGUCUUCAUUGUGAAACACCAAAUUUCCUGGAAGAGCAAUGGGAACGUGAAAAUGCACCCAGGAAACCCCGCUAGGAAGCGCCUGGGGCAGUUUGCAUACUUCUGUGACGAAGGAUAGGUUUCUAAGGUAAACGGAGUCACUCGAAUGUCAUCUCUGGGUGCAGGUGUAACCAGUGCCAAAAAGAUGCGCGAGGUCAGACCUUCACCAUCCAAAACUGUGAAGUACACUGCCACGGUGACGAAGGGGGCUGUCACAUACACCAAAGCCAAGAGAGAACUGGUCAAGGACACCAAACCCAAUCACCACAAGCCCAGUUCCGCUGUCAACCACACAAUCUCAGGGAAAACUGAAAGUAGCAAUGCAAAAACCCGCAAACAGGUGCUAUCCCUCGGGGGGGCGUCCAAGUCCACUGGGCCCGCCGUCAAUGGCCUCAAGGUCAGUGGCAGGUUGAACCCAAAGUCAUGCACUAAGGAGGUGGGGGGGCGGCAGCUGCGGGAGGGCCUGCAGCUGCGGGAGGGGCUGCGGAACUCCAAGAGGAGACUGGAAGAGGCACACCAGGCGGAGAAGCCGCAGUCGCCCCCCAAGAAGAUGAAAGGGGCGGCUGGCCCCGCCGAAGGCCCUGGCAAGAAGGCCCCGGCCGAGAGAGGUCUGCUGAACGGACACGUGAAGAAGGAAGUGCCGGAGCGCAGUCUGGAGAGGAAUCGGCCGAAGCGGGCCACGGCCGGGAAGAGCACGCCAGGCAGACAAGCACAUGGCAAGGCGGACAGCGCCUCCUGUGAAAAUCGUUCUACCUCGCAACCGGAGUCCGUGCACAAGCCGCAGGACUCGGGCAAGGCCGAGAAGGGCGGCGGCAAGGCCGGGUGGGCGGCCAUGGACGAGAUCCCCGUCCUCAGGCCCUCCGCCAAGGAGUUCCACGAUCCGCUCAUCUACAUCGAGUCGGUCCGCGCUCAGGUGGAGAAGUUCGGGAUGUGCAGGGUGAUCCCCCCUCCGGACUGGCGGCCCGAGUGCAAGCUCAACGAUGAGAUGCGGUUUGUCACGCAGAUUCAGCACAUCCACAAGCUGGGCCGGCGCUGGGGCCCCAACGUGCAGCGGCUGGCCUGCAUCAAGAAGCACCUCAAAUCUCAGGGCAUCACCAUGGACGAGCUCCCGCUCAUAGGGGGCUGUGAGCUCGACCUGGCCUGCUUUUUCCGGCUGAUUAAUGAGAUGGGCGGCAUGCAGCAAGUGACUGACCUCAAAAAAUGGAACAAACUAGCAGACAUGCUGCGCAUCCCCAGAACUGCCCAGGACCGGCUGGCCAAGCUGCAGGAGGCCUACUGCCAGUACCUACUCUCCUACGACUCCCUGUCCCCAGAGGAGCACCGGCGGCUGGAGAAGGAGGUGCUGAUGGAGAAGGAGAUCCUGGAGAAGCGCAAGGGGCCGCUGGAAGGCCACACAGAGAACGACCACCACAAGUUCCACCCUCUGCCCCGCUUCGAGCCCAAGAAUGGGCUCAUCCACGGCGUGGCCCCCAGGAACGGCUUCCGCAGCAAGCUCAAGGAGGUGGGCCAGGCCCAGUUGAAGACUGGCCGGCGGCGACUCUUCGCUCAGGAAAAAGAAGUGGUCAAGGAAGAGGAGGAGGACAAAGGCGUCCUCAAUGACUUCCACAAGUGCAUCUAUAAGGGAAGGUCUGUUUCUCUAACAACUUUUUAUCGAACAGCGAGGAAUAUCAUGAGCAUGUGUUUCAGCAAGGAGCCUGCCCCAGCCGAAAUCGAGCAAGAGUACUGGAGGCUAGUGGAAGAGAAGGACUGCCACGUGGCAGUGCACUGCGGCAAGGUGGACACCAACACUCACGGCAGUGGAUUCCCAGUAGGAAAAUCAGAACCCUUUUCGAGGCAUGGAUGGAACCUCACCGUCCUCCCCAAUAACACAGGGUCCAUCCUGCGUCACCUCGGUGCUGUGCCUGGAGUGACUAUUCCCUGGCUAAAUAUUGGCAUGGUCUUUUCUACCUCAUGCUGGUCUCGAGACCAAAAUCACCUUCCAUACAUUGACUACUUACACACUGGUGCUGACUGCAUUUGGUAUUGCAUUCCUGCUGAGGAGGAGAACAAGCUGGAAGAUGUGGUCCACACCCUGCUGCAAGCCAAUGGCACCCCAGGGCUGCAGAUGCUGGAAAGCAACGUCAUGAUCUCCCCGGAGGUGCUGUGCAAAGAGGGGAUCAAGGUGCACAGGACCGUGCAGCAGAGUGGCCAGUUUGUCGUCUGCUUCCCGGGAUCCUUUGUGUCCAAAGUGUGCUGUGGGUACAGCGUGUCUGAAACCGUGCACUUUGCUACCACCCAGUGGACAAGUAUGGGCUUUGAGACCGCCAAGGAAAUGAAGCGUCGCCAUAUAGCUAAGCCAUUCUCCAUGGAGAAGUUACUCUACCAGAUUGCACAAGCAGAAGCAAAAAAAGAAAACGGUCCCACUCUCAGUACCAUCUCAGCCCUCCUGGAUGAGCUCAGGGAUACAGAGCUGCGGCAGCGCAGGCAGCUGUUCGAGGCUGGCCUCCACUCCUCCGCACGCUAUGGCAGCCACGAUGGCAGCAGCACGGUGGCGGACGGGAAGAAAAAGCCUCGAAAGUGGCUGCAGUUGGAGACGUCAGAGAGGAGGUGUCAGAUCUGCCAGCACCUGUGCUACCUGUCCAUGGUGGUACAAGAGAACGAAAACGUCGUGUUCUGUCUGGAGUGUGCUCUGCGCCACGUGGAGAAACAGAAGUCCUGCCGAGGGCUGAAGUUGAUGUACCGCUACGAUGAGGAACAGAUUAUCAGUCUGGUCAAUCAGAUCUGCGGCAAAGUGUCUGGUAAAAACGGCAGCAUUGAGAACUGUCUCAGUAAACCCACACCAAAAAGAGGUCCCCGCAAGAGAGCGACAGUGGACGUGCCCCCCUCCCGUCUGUCAGCCUCCAGUUCAUCCAAAAGUGCUUCGAGCUCAUCAUGAAGAUGCCAACGCCCGUGGUCGAUUUAUAUAUAUUUUUUUGUAAUUAUUAUAUUCUAGUUUGGAGUACUUGCUGUAGGAUUCAAGCUGUCUUUGCACUAGCUCUAAAGAAGAUUUUCUUCUGGUUUUAGAGAACUAAUUUUGUUUUAGCAUUAAACUGUUGAACUUUUUUUUGUACUUAGAAAACCUAGAUACUGCAGUCAGAUUUUGGAAACUGCCGUAUAGUCACUGUUUUAAAAACCCCGGAGGGGCUGUAUUAAUUUGUAUUGCCCCAUGGCUGACAAAAGCCUUUUUUUUUGGUUUUGAUUUUUUUUUUUUUGUAACUGUUGGGGGGAAAAAGGCUUUUUAACCCAUUUUUGAAGAGGGUGAAGUUUGGAGAACAAAUUUAAAAACCAUCAGUCAUGUGAGCAGAUUUUUUAGAAGGGAUAGGAGACACACGCGCACACACACACACACACGAAACUUGAAAUGGCUUUGCUUUGGCUGUCGUCUUCUGCCGUGUGCCAGAUGAGCUUGUGAUCUGGGAAGCCGGGGCACCCCCGUUUUGUUUCUCUGGGCGGUUGUGGCAGCUGAAGGCGGACGUUGUUUCCUAACCAUAGGUGGAACGAGGAGACGGGAGCGAGUGGGCUCUCCACCAGCACAUCACUAUGCAUCUGUUCCAGGAAAGAAGAAAAGCGAGCGAGGAAGACGGAAAAGACUGCCUGCCUUGGAGGGGUCACAUGAGGGAGACCUGUGCCUGAUUUCAUUAGGAAAUCCAUUCUGUUAUUUUUUGGUGCUGUUGGCUACUUUAUCAAAAAACCCUUCAAUAGCAUCCUUAAGAUUUAAAAAAAAAAAAAAAAAAAAGGAAAAAAAAGUGAUGGAAGCCGUAAGUGCUUCUUUGUCAUCGACGUGCAAUCUUUCUAACAUUCCAUCUCCAUCUCACCGCUUCUUGUUUGACACCUUCACAAGUCAGCAUUAAUCUUUCUUUUAAAACUUGUUUCAUUUAUGAUCAUGUAGAGAGCCACUAGGAGGCCUGCAGUUAUUUUUGAAUGUGAAAAUGCAUUUGCGUUCAUCUUGUCUAUUUUUUCUCUUCAUGUUGUAACAAAAAGGAAAAAAGAAAAAAAAAUCCCAUCCCUUUUGUACAUAUGCCUGUAAAUUGUUUUAAAUACUUGAGCCUUUUUCUCGGUGGGGGGUGGGGAGGGGGGUGAGAAGACAAGAUGAAGAAAAGCCUUACAUUUCAGUUUCUUCAUCGGUUGGAUUGGAUGCUUACAGGGUUUUUCUUGUAACAUUUAUAAGUGCUGCUUACAUCACUGAACAACAACAAAAAAAUAAUAAUGGAGUAGCUGUUGCCCUUCUCCGGUUGUGUGUACAGUAUGUGUGGAAUAAAAAAGGGAAACUGUUUUCACAAGCUGUUCUUUGUUUCAUAAUUGGAUUCAUCAAUCCCGUAGCUACCCAUAUUGCACUGAGCUUGCCAGUGGUGACUGCCAGGAACGUCCUAUGAUCCACUUUGUUGGUUGUUGUUGCAGAAGACUGAACUGUUUUGGAAUAUUUAACAAUUACAGAAACAGUCAAGUGUUUUCCAAUGUGGUUGUCCGGUUUCUAUGGCCUUGCUGUGUACUUUCCCUCUUUUUGACAGUAAACUUCUGCCUAUGGCUUACAGUUUGACAUUUAAUUUAUUAGCGCUGCUCUGCACCCCUCCCUUGGGAGGGAGACUUCAUGUGGUUUAUUGCGAGUUUUUUGUUUACUUUUCAGGUUUGUACUACAAGGUUUAAUAAUAAAAACAAAGUUUUUUGGACAUUUGUCUGUCUUGUGGAA